ACUGGCGGGCGGGAUCCCUCCGCUCUGGGGAGGCAGCGCUGGCGGCGGGGCUGGGGCCACUGAGGAAAUCCAUCCGCGCCGCCGCCGCCGCCGCCGCCGCCGCCGCCGCCGCCUCCGCCGCGGAGGAAGACAGCGCCGCCCGCGCACCGCCAGCGACCUCCGCCGCAGAGUCCCACCGCCACAGGCCUCGGGCCAGCGGCCAGGAGCUGCCUCCCCCAGCCCCCGUCCCGCGGCCCCCAGCCGCCCCCAACCCUGCCCCACGGGCCCGGCGCCAUGAGUGAGCUGGAGCAACUGAGACAGGAGGCCGAGCAGCUCCGGAACCAGAUCCGGGAUGCCCGAAAAGCAUGUGGGGACUCAACACUGACCCAGAUCACAGCUGGGCUGGACCCAGUGGGGAGAAUCCAGAUGAGGACCCGGAGGACCCUCCGUGGGCACCUGGCAAAGAUCUAUGCCAUGCACUGGGGGACCGACUCAAGGCUGCUGGUCAGCGCCUCCCAGGAUGGGAAGCUCAUCAUCUGGGACAGCUACACCACCAACAAGGUCCACGCCAUCCCGCUGCGCUCCUCCUGGGUAAUGACCUGUGCCUACGCGCCCUCAGGGAACUUUGUGGCCUGUGGGGGGUUGGACAACAUCUGCUCCAUCUACAGCCUCAAGACCCGCGAGGGCAACGUCAGGGUCAGCCGGGAGCUGCCUGGCCACACUGGGUACCUGUCGUGUUGCCGCUUCCUGGAUGACAACCAAAUCAUCACCAGCUCUGGGGAUACCACCUGUGCCCUGUGGGACAUUGAGACAGGCCAGCAGACAGUGGGUUUUGCUGGACACAGUGGGGAUGUGAUGUCCCUGUCCCUGGCCCCCGAUGGCCGCACGUUUGUGUCAGGCGCCUGUGAUGCCUCUAUCAAGCUGUGGGACGUGCGGGAUUCCAUGUGCCGACAGACCUUCAUCGGCCAUGAAUCCGACAUCAAUGCAGUGGCUUUCUUCCCCAACGGCUACGCCUUCACCACCGGCUCUGACGACGCCACGUGCCGCCUCUUCGACCUGCGGGCCGAUCAGGAGCUCCUCAUGUACUCCCAUGACAACAUCAUCUGUGGCAUCACCUCUGUUGCCUUCUCGCGCAGCGGACGGCUGCUGCUCGCUGGCUACGACGACUUCAACUGCAACAUCUGGGAUGCCAUGAAGGGCGACCGUGCAGGAGUCCUCGCUGGCCACGACAACCGCGUGAGCUGCCUCGGGGUCACCGACGAUGGCAUGGCUGUGGCCACGGGCUCCUGGGACUCCUUCCUCAAGAUCUGGAACUAAUGGCCCCACCCCCACUGGGCCCAGGCCAGGAGGGGCCCUGCCCAUGCCCACACUACAGGCCAGGGCUGCGGGGCUGGCGCAAUCCCAGCCCCCUUCCCCGGGCCACGGGGCCUUGGGUCCCUGCCCUCCCACCCAGGUUUGGUUCCUCCCGGGGCCCCCACUGUGGAGAUAAGAAGGGGAUGGAAUGGGGGAAGAGGAGGAGCAGGAGGCCCUCAUCCUUCUGCUGCCCUGGGGUUGGGGCCUCACCCCUCUGGAGGGCCGGAGGCAGGAGGUGGAAACCCCAGGGGCUGGCUUUUUUAAAACUGGUUUUAUUUUAAUUUUUAUUAUAUUUUCAGUUUUUCCAUAAAGGAGCCAAUUCCAACUCUGUA